ACCCUGGGAGGAAGCCGACUAGGCGAAUUCACUUACUGACCGGCCUGGGCUGCUCUGAGACAUGGAGGAAGCCAGUGAAGGUGGAGGAAAUGAUCGUGUGCGGAACCUGCAAAGUGAGGUGGAGGGAGUUAAGAAUAUUAUGACCCAGAAUGUGGAGCGGAUCCUGGCCCGGGGGGAAAACUUGGAACAUCUCCGCAACAAGACAGAGGAUCUGGAAGCCACACCAGGGGCUGAGGCCAGCUGUUUCAGGGAGGAAGUAACUCCAAAGUUGAGCAAAGUCUGGAGCCUCAAGUUCUGUGUUCAGCGGGGAGGCUGGCUCUGGCUUUCUGAGUCCUGUGUGAACUCUUGGCUCUUGGUCUGAGCACUUCAAGACGACAUCGCAGAAGGUGGCUCGAAAAUUCUGGUGGAAGAACGUGAAGAUGAUUGUCCUUAUCUGCGUGAUUGUUUUUAUCAUCAUCCUCUUCAUUGUGCUCUUUGCCACUGGUGCCUUCUCUUAAGUAACAGGGAACCUCUCCCACCUGCCCUUCUCUUCAGGGACAACCCUCCAUAAAUGUGUGCCAAGAGGGUCUCCUUUCCUGUCUUCCUCUACAGAGAAUGCUGCUCGGUCCUCCUACCCCUCUUCCCGAGGCCCUGCUGCCAUGUUGUAUGCCCCAGAAGGUACCUUGGUCCCCCGGAAGGAGAGAAAAAAGAGAGAUGGACUGUGGCUGCAUUUCUUGGGUCCUUAGAGUGGGCUGGAGAGACCUAGAGGGCCCAGCAUGUGGCUGGGAAACUGUUGGUGGCCAGUGGGUAAUAAAGACCUUUCAGUAUCCCUA